GGAGGCACUUCCGCUCCAGGAAGGCGAGGUCGGAUCUGAGAUAUCUCCCAGGGAGGUUCACUUCCCCGGAACUCUGCCUUUUCCCAGAAGGAGGAGGGGAAAAAUGACCAAGUUCCAGGAGGCAGUGACAUUCAAGGAUGUGGCUGUGGCCUUCACUGAGGAGGAGCUGGGGCUGCUGGACUCUGCCCAGAGGAAGCUGUACCGAGAUGUGAUGCUGGAGAACUUUAGGAACCUGGUUUCAGUGGGACAUCAGUCCUUCAAACCAGAUAUGAUAUCCCAGUUGGAGAGGGAAGAAAAGCUUUGGAUGAAGGAGCUUCAAACCCAAAGAGGUAAGCAUUCAGGAGACAGGAAUCAAAAUGAGAUGGCAACUCUUCACAAAGCAGGAUUAAGGUGCUUUUCACUGGGAGAGCUUUCAUGCUGGCAAAUCAAGAGACACAUUGCGAGCAAAUUAGCCAGAAGUCAAGACUCCAUGAUAAAUAUUGAAGGAAAGAGCUCUCAGUUCCCCAAGCACCAUGAUUCCCCCUGUCAAGUGGGAGCAGGAGAAUCUAUUCAAGCUUCUGUGGAUGACAACUGUCUAGUGAAUCACAUAGGGGAUCAUUCCAGUAUCAUUGAAAAUCAAGAAUUUCCAACUGGGAAAGUUCCGAAUUCUUGGAGUAAAAUAUAUCUGAAUGAGACACAGAAUUAUCAGAGAAGUUGUAAGCAGACUCAGAUGAAAAACAAACUAUGUAUAUUUGCUCCAUAUGUUGACAUUUUCAGUUGUAUUUCACACCACCAUGAUGAUAAUAUAGUGCACAAAAGAGAUAAAGUUCAUAGCAAUAGUGAUUGUGGUAAAGAUACCCUAAAGGUAUCACCUCUUACCCAGCGUAGUAUUCACACAGGACAGAAAACCUACCAGGGUAAUGAAUGUGAAGAAGCCUUCAAUGAUAGCUCCAGUCUUGAACUUCAUAAACAGGUACACUUGGGAAAGAAGUCUCCAGCGUGUAGUACACAUGAGAAGGACACCAGUUAUAGCUCAGGUAUUCCUGUUCAACAAAGUGUUCGUACUGGGAAAAAACGCUAUUGGUGUCAUGAAUGUGGUAAAGGUUUCAGUCAGAGCUCAAAUCUGCAAACUCAUCAGAGAGUCCACACAGGGGAGAAACCCUAUACAUGCCACGAGUGUGGUAAGAGCUUUAAUCAGAGCUCACAUCUUUAUGCUCAUUUGCCUAUUCACACAGGAGAGAAGCCCUAUAGAUGUGACAGUUGUGGGAAGGGCUUCAGUCGUAGCACAGAUCUUAACAUUCAUUGCAGAGUUCACACUGGAGAGAAACCUUAUAAAUGUGAGGUGUGUGGGAAGGGCUUCACUCAGAGAUCACAUCUUCAGGCCCAUGAAAGAAUUCACACUGGAGAGAAACCAUAUAAAUGUGGGGAUUGUGGUAAACGCUUUAGUUGUAGCUCAAAUCUUCAUACCCAUCAGAGAGUCCACACUGAAGAAAAACCAUACAAAUGUGAUGAGUGUGGUAAGUGCUUUAGUUUGAGCUUUAAUCUUCAUAGUCAUCAACGAGUCCACACAGGAGAAAAACCAUAUAAAUGUGAAGAGUGUGGUAAGGGUUUUAGUUCAGCCUCAAGUUUCCAGAGCCAUCAGAGGGUCCAUACAGGAGAGAAACCAUUUCGAUGCAACGUGUGUGGGAAAGGCUUCAGUCAGAGUUCAUACUUUCAAGCACAUCAGAGAGUCCACACUGGAGAAAAACCAUACAAAUGUGAAGUGUGUGGGAAGCGCUUCAAUUGGAGCUUGAAUCUUCACAAUCAUCAGAGAGUCCACACCGGAGAGAAACCCUACAAAUGUGAAGAGUGUGGUAAGGGUUUCAGUCAGGCUUCAAAUCUUCAAGCCCAUCAGAGCGUCCACACUGGGGAAAAACCAUUCAAGUGUGAUGCAUGUCAGAAGCGAUUCAGUCAGGCCUCACACCUUCAAGCCCAUCAGAGAGUCCACACCGGAGAGAAACCAUAUAAAUGUGACACUUGUGGUAAGGCCUUCAGCCAGAGGUCAAAUCUUCAAGUCCAUCAGAUAAUUCACACUGGAGAGAAACCAUUUAAAUGUGAGGAAUGUGGGAAAGAAUUCAGUUGGAGUGCUGGUCUCAGUGCCCAUCAGAGGGUCCACACAGGAGAGAAACCCUAUACGUGUCAGCAGUGUGGGAAGGGCUUCAGUCAGGCCUCACAUUUUCACACACACCAGAGAGUCCACACUGGAGAGAGGCCUUACAUAUGUGAUGUCUGUUGUAAGGGCUUCAGUCAGAGGUCACAUCUCAUCUACCAUCAGAGAGUCCACACUGGAGGGAAUCUGUAGAAAUGAGAGGUGUGGUUCAGCCUUCAGUUAGAGCUCACAUCUUUGUCUCCGUUGGGAAGUCCAUGCUGAUGAUUGUGAAAAGUUCCUUUAAAACUAGAAGCUUCAAAGAAUCUUGACAGGAAAGAAGUCUCUCAAAUGCUGUGUUUUAGACUUGGUUAGGACAUGAAUUCUUUACAAACGUCAUAUUUCACAGAUGCGAGAAAACUUUGUUCUGUAAAUAUGAUCAGUGUUUAUAUCAGAGUACCAGGUGUCCCGGUUCUCAAGAUGUAACACAGCAGAAAAGUCUUGUCGGAGUCUGCACAGGAGAGAGGCCUUCCUUUAACAAAAGUAUGAUUGACAGAAAAAAUGGAUGUCAACUAAAAUGUAACCUCUAUGUAAGGAGGUGUUUUUCACCACUCUAUCUCUACCAUGUAGAAUUGUGCUUGGCUCAUAAUAGGGCCCAGCAAUUACUGAAGAAAGUGAAGAAAAUACCUAUAAUUAGGACAAAUACUUGAAAAUUCUAGUCUGUUUUCUACUCUAAAUUUAUAUUAAUUUAUAUUCAAAAGGAAUCCUGCAAGUAGCCUUAAUAACGUUAGUUUCAGUAAGUACUGAAAAGUAUAUAAUACUGCCAUCCAUACUAACACAAAUUUGGAAAAAAGACAUGAAUGGCUCCCAUCCUUCAGCCUUAGUUCUUUGUACAGUGUAUCAUCAGUUGUGUACAGUAUGAUUUUUAGUGUCAGUUUAUAGACUGAACAAUACUGUUUUUAUCUAAUGUGACCCUGCAAUUUACAUGAUUAGAAUUUUUGGACACUAAGCUGUACUGUAACUCUGAAAGUGUUAAAAGUAGUUACUGAUGACAAAAAGUUUCUUAGUAAACUUGAAUUGUUAAUA